AUUCCACCCCCAGUGGUUAUUAAUUUCAGAACACAUCUGAAUUCCUUCUCUGUGGCAUAUGCUUUAGGAGAGGAGCAGACAGCUCUUAGCUAGGGUCAGAUUUCAAAUUCUCAUCUCUUGGUGCCAAUACCACCACCAGAUUCUUCUUUGAAGUCAACUUUUGAGAUCUUCACUAAGUACACGUUGGUGUCUGAAGAUUCACACGAGUGCCUCUGGUAAUCAUUUUCUUCAGGGAAUCACAGUCUCUCCUCUCAGCAAAGCAUCCACUGUACUGAACUUUGCUUUUGGAAACAUCUUCUUCCUGAGACCUCGUUGAAAGAAACUCUCUGGUGUCAUACUUUCCAAUAUGGAGGUGAAGAACUUUGCAGUUUGGGAUUAUGUUGUAUUUGCAGCCCUCUUUUUCAUUUCCUCUGGAAUUGGGGUGUUCUUUGCCAUUAAGGAGAGAAAAAAGGCAACUUCCCGAGAGUUCCUGGUUGGGGGAAGGCAAAUGAGCUUUGGCCCUGUCGGCUUGUCUCUGACAGCCAGCUUCAUGUCAGCUGUCACGGUCCUGGGGACCCCUUCUGAAGUCUACCGCUUUGGGGCAUCCUUCCUAGUCUUCUUCAUUGCUUACCUAUUUGUCAUCCUCUUAACAUCAGAGCUCUUUCUCCCUGUGUUCUACAGAUCUGGUAUCACCAGCACUUAUGAGUACUUACAACUACGAUUCAACAAACCAGUUCGCUAUGCUGCCACGGUCAUCUACAUUGUACAGACGAUUCUCUACACAGGAGUGGUGGUGUAUGCUCCUGCCCUGGCACUCAAUCAAGUGACUGGGUUUGAUCUCUGGGGCUCUGUGUUUGCAACAGGAAUUGUUUGCACAUUCUACUGUACCCUGGGAGGAUUAAAAGCAGUGGUGUGGACAGAUGCAUUUCAGAUGGUUGUCAUGAUUGUGGGCUUCUUAACGGUUCUCAUUCAAGGAUCAACUCAUGCUGGGGGAUUCCACAAUGUAUUAGAGCAAUCAACAAAUGGAUCUCGACUACAUAUAUUUGACUUUGAUGUAGAUCCUCUCAGGCGACACACUUUUUGGACUAUCACAGUGGGAGGAACUUUUACUUGGCUCGGAAUCUAUGGGGUCAAUCAAUCAACUAUUCAGCGAUGCAUCUCUUGCAAAACAGAAAAGCAUGCUAAGCUUGCCUUGUAUUUUAACUUGCUGGGUCUCUGGAUCAUUCUGGUGUGUGCUGUCUUCUCUGGCUUAAUCAUGUACUCUCACUUUAAAGACUGUGACCCUUGGACUUCUGGCAUCAUCUCAGCACCAGACCAGCUGAUGCCGUACUUUGUCAUGGAGAUAUUUGCCACAAUGCCAGGACUGCCAGGACUUUUUGUGGCUUGUGCCUUCAGUGGAACUCUGAGCACCGUGGCUUCCAGCAUCAAUGCCUUGGCAACAGUGACCUUUGAGGAUUUUGUCAAGAGCUGUUUUCCUCAUCUCUCCGACAAGCUGAGCACCUGGAUCAGUAAAGGCUUAUGUCUCUUAUUUGGCGUGAUGUGUACCUCUAUGGCUGUGGCUGCAUCUGUCAUGGGAGGUGUUGUGCAGGCUUCCCUCAGCAUUCACGGCAUGUGUGGAGGACCAAUGCUGGGCUUAUUCUCCCUGGGAAUCGUGUUCCCUUUUGUGAAUUGGAAGGGUGCACUAGGAGGUCUUCUUACUGGAAUCACCUUGUCAUUUUGGGUGGCCAUUGGGGCCUUCAUUUACCCUGCACCAGCCUCUAAGACAUGGCCUUUGCCUCUGUCAACAGACCAAUGUAUCAAAUCAAAUGUGACAGCAACAGGGCCUCCAGUACUAUCCAGCAGACCUGGAAUAGCUGAUACCUGGUACUCGAUCUCCUACCUUUACUACAGUGCAGUGGGCUGCUUAGGAUGCAUUGUUGCUGGAGUAAUCAUCAGCCUCAUAACAGGUCGCCAAAGAGGUGAGGAUAUUCAACCACUGUUAAUUAGACCAGUUUGUAAUUUAUUUUGCUUUUGGUCUAAGAAGUACAAAACACUAUGCUGGUGUGGAGUUCAGCAUGACAGUGGGACAGAGCAGGAAAACCUUGAGAAUGGCAGUGCCCGGAAACAGGGGGCUGAAUCUGUCUUACAGAACGGACUCAGAAGAGAAAGCCUGGUACAUGUUCCAGGCUAUGAUCCUAAGGACAAAAGCUACAACAAUAUGGCAUUUGAGACUACCCAUUUCUAAGGCAAUACCUGUAUGAAUGCACACACACACGUGCAAUACACACACACACACACAAACUCCACAUACUUCUUGCCUACUUGUUAGUAGAUAUGUAUAGUUGCCAUUGCUAGAAGACAGGGAUGUCUGGUGCCUAUUUCUACUUAUUUAUAACUACAUGCAAAAUGACUGUCUCUCGGGAUAUUCUUUGAAAGACUCCAACUUUCACAGAGAAAAACCAACCUGCUCCAAAUGCCCUUGACUACUUCCUUCUUGAAUAAAUUAGGGCUGGAUUUCAUUACCAUUCAAGAAAGCGAAGUCUUUUUGCUUGGUGUCAUAUUAAACUUCAGGUUUUUCGUUUUAGUAGUUUUUUAACCAUCAAAAUAUCUUGGAGUUUAGAGGCAGAACGGGAAACAGAAAUAUGCAUAUUUAACACUUUCCUGCCACGAGGGAUAAAAUAGAGGAAUGACAUCCACCCCUGACCUCAUACCUGACAUACAUGUAGAUAUAUUUUAUGCCACCCAUCUCCCAUCCUGUAGCUACAAUUGGCAUACAACUACUAUUAACCUCCCUUCACCACCACUGUCAGGUCCUCUUCCAGUCAUUCCAGUCAUUAGCUGUCCUGACCAAACAUUAAAAAAAAAAUUCAGCUAAAUACAGAAGAAGAUGGUAUGUCUGGCUAGUGGGAGUGAUUAUAACUAAAAACUUUGCUCCUUUUGUGCUGUCCAUGCAGUAUGUCUUCUUCCUUUCUAUCACUUUACAAUGAAAAAUUGCCUCAGAGCUCAAUAAGAAGUCUAGAGCCUUUUUCCAGGGCUAAGGAAAGAGAAAAGGAAUGUCCUAUAGAAGGUUGUUAGGAUAGAAUUUGGUAAAAGAACGUUGCAAAUAUUGUAACAGACCAUAGGAGAUUUCAUCAGCAAUAGGAUUCUUCUUUGGAGAAAAUACAUUGUCCAUAAGACUUGUACUCUGCUCAUUCAACUCAUGUGAGCAAGCUCAACUCACUCCACCUGGGUUAGGUAACAGAAGUGGAGAACUUCAUAGUUCGUGUCUAGAAAAUAAUGUUUAAAGUUCUGGAGAAUGAGGGUAUUGCAGAUUAAAAGGCGAGUUGACAAAUGAAGGAGCAGUGAAAGAUUUUUGGAAGAAGUGAAGAAGUGAAAUUCUGAAAAGGUAAAAGAAAGAACCAGUAUGUCACAGGGGCCAAGUCAGAGGACAGAUAAUAAGAAACAAAGUUGUAUCUGAGAGUCAUAUAUUAGGACAGGUGUCAGAUAUUUAUUUUGGUGGCCAGAUAAAAGCAAAAGGCCUAGAAACAGUGUGUUAGCAAAGUAAGAAGAAAUGGUCCAAAUAGGCAAGGAUAAGGAAAUCCAAAGGUUGUCUUUAAAUAUUUCUCAAAAGAGAAAGCCUUGAAAGAAGCAUACAAUAGAGAAAAAAUAAAUUACCAGUAUUUAUUAUUAGAAAAGAUAGAAAGACAGACAAAUCAGUGGAGGAAUUAAAACAGAGAAACUGGAGUUUAUAAAACAGAGCCCAAUCCUUGCCUUCUCUCCCUCCACUCAAAUAGAAAAGGAGAAUGGAGAAAGAGAAAGAAGGUAUUAGGCUACAGUUUAUAAGAGAGAUGAGAAAAAAAUACAUUUGGGAAUAGAGGGAAAGGGUCAAAAGGGGUCACAUUUGGAGAAAUAUCUGAAAAUGAGAAGGAGCAGAAUUUUUGGAAACAUUUUUUAAAGUCUGGCAACGCUAAUUAAGCUGUUGAUCUAAGGAUUUGCAAAUUGAGAGGUGCAAUUAUUUUCCAAAUGAUUUGUGACACUCUUAUUAAUUAGAAUAUAUAUUUUGUGAAUAUUGAAAUCUGAGCCAAAACUAGUUAGCUUUAUUAAUAUCUUAGGGAAAGAAGAGAGAAAGAAAGAGGGAGGGAGAGAGAGAAAGAAAGAAAGAAAGAAAGAAAGAAAGAAAAGAAGAAAGAAAGAAAGAAAAAGACAGGAAGAGGAAGAGAGAGACAGAAAGAAUAAAAAAACAGCAAUUCUGAGGAUGAGAAUAAAUUAAUGGUAGGUAUUACAUAUGCAUAUACAUAUAUAUAUCUGUACACAUAUAUAUGUAAAUAUGAUUUGGAAUACAUCAGGAUUGUGAACUUCCACUUGGGAUAGCAUAAAAGCAAAAUAUACCAUACAAUUUUUCAUUUUACUCACAAAUUUUACUCACAAAUUCUCCUAAAGACAUUUCACUAGGUCAGUACAUUUCCGAGAAAGUUUUAAAAACGUUUCUUCUUUUAUAGUCCCUAAUUAUCUUACCUGGAGUGUUAUCAAAAUGUCAUACAACUGGAAAAUGCAAUUAUUAUUAUAAAAAUAUCUCUGCCUUCUCUUGUGUAAUGAAAUUUAUGGCAUUAGGAGAUGACAUUUCAAGAGAUUUUAGAGGUCAAUGUAGAGACUCCCCCCAUUCUUCUUAAUUGAACAAACAUGCAUAAAUCUAGGGUUUCAGGUAGAGAGCAGAUGGGAAUCUACAGGAAACUGUCUUCCAUAGUGUAUGAAAACCGUGUUUGUUGUGUGGUGAAGCAAAAGGAAACUAUGAAGCGCACAGUCAAUAGAUUCAGCUAGUGAGUCCCAGCACUCCUUUCAGGCCCUCACUAGGAUUAGCAGCCCAGAGUCAUGCCAAGGCCACUGGUGCAGUACAAAGACAGUUCAGUGACAAGUUCCAUCCAUACCAUGGAAGAGGGUUAAACUUGUGGCUGUUUUUGCCACAGCAUGACCAGAGACAUUCUCAAUAAAUGGCACUAGGAAUGAUGAGUUUUAGAGGGGCCUAAAAUGUUCCAAACUUGAUACUCACCACUGUACCUUUAAAGCACAACCACAGAUAUUGGUAAAAAUGGAACAGAAUUACCUCAAUACCUCUUUAACUCAUUCUGUAUGAAUUCAUUUUGAUGACAGACAUUUUUUGUCACCAUUUGGAAUAAGAACUACAACAGCUUAUGAUUGAGGUGAGGAACUGCAGUCAAAUGGCUUAGGUUCAAACACGAGUUCUGACACAAAUCUAGGUAAUUUUGGGCAAUAUUUUAAAAUCUUAGUUUAUUCACCAAUUAAUAGGAGUAAAAAUUACCCCUACUUAAUAGAAUUAUUAUGAAGAUUUAUAUAAGUAAAUCAUAUAAAGUGCUUAGCACAGUGUGACUGGCCCACAUGGAACAUUUAAUACUUGGUCUGCAGUAUAUGAAGAAAAUGGUGUACAUGUUAACUUAAAUGGUUUCAUUAUUUCUCUUCAGGAUUUUUAAGAUGUGGGAUCAGAAUAUAUGUUACUAUUUUGAGAAUUAGAAAUAAUAAGAAAAACAGAAUGUAUACAUUAAAAGUCAUGCCUAAAUUUCCAAAGAGUAGUUUUUUUAAUGCCAGAGUUUAAAUAAAAUAUUAUUUUCCAGAGAGUAACUUUUCUAAAGGUCCUAAAUUCUGAAAAGAGAGAAAACUACUGUUAUAAACAAGUUUAUUACUAAAAGAUGCAAUUCAUUACUAUGAUUUAUUAUUAUUUUGUACAUGUAAACCUUGAUAAAUAAACAGCAUCUCAACCCAAGUUUAUUACUCAUUGCACAGUUCAAAGCAACUAUGACUCUCAAAAUAGCAACAGAAGGUGGGGAGGGUCUUUUCCCUUUGUUUAUAUAGUAUUUGCUAAAAAUGAACUUUACUAUUUUGUGGCUUUAUAGGGUUACACCAUUUCAUUCUAAAGAGAAACAAAAAGUAAACCAUUGGCCAUGUGGCUUUCAAACAGUAUUUCAAAGAGAAUAUUACUGAAAUAUUUUUGUGCUGUUACAGUCUUAAUCAAACAUUAUUACAAAGAUCAGAUACGGAAAAAAUAGAGGAGUCUCCCCUUAAUUGUUCCCUUUGAAAUAAAUUGUUUUAAAUUAUUACAGAAGUUAUAGCUGUAUGUACAUGCACAUUUGUAUAUUUACAAGUCUCAUGUACUUAAUCUCAAUAUUGCAAAUUAGCUAGGUUUACUAUAGAGUUAACUGCUUUUAUCUAGCAUUUAUAAUCUUGUAGUAUAACCUAUUUUCAAAUAACUAAAAUUUAAUUGAUGUCAUCAAUGGUACACAUGAAAAUGAUACAAAUUUAUAAACUAAUAAAAUGUAACUCGUCAUUGAUAGUAAA